AGGCUGGAGUGAGAGGUGUGGACUUCGGGAGAUUCUGCCGGAAGUGUGUGGGCGGGACGCUGUUUCGACACUGCAGGUAGGGUGUAAGGAUUGCUCAUCGGGUCCCCUCUUCUGCUCUCCUUUCCUCCCUCACCACAUCUGCCCAUGGUGGCCCCUCCUACGGUCCCAAAUCCCCCACCACCUGGCACAACAGUCCCCUUUGGGGUUCGGGUAACACUGGACUAUUUUAUUUAUUUAUUUAUUUAUUUAUUUAUUUAUUUAUUUAUUUAUUUUUACUGUAGCGGGGAGAAGGCAAGAAACCAUAAUGCAAAUGAUUUAUGUUGAUACACAUUAGAAAACGAUUAGUCAGAUAAUCAGUUUCAACCACAUUUAUCUAGGGUUUAGUAUUUUUAUAUUACUACAUUCAAUUUUAAUAACCCUCUAGGCAAACAUUAUUACCUUCAUUUUACAGAGAAAGAAAUGUAAACUGACUUUCCAAAUGUAAAGUGACUUUCCAAAGGUCACAAAGCUAGAAAGUAUCACGUUAAGGACGAUCCCAGUCUCCUGGCUUAAAGCCCUACGCUCCUCCCACACCUCAUGCCAAGACCAAGAUCUGCAGCCACGGUCCUUCACCCAUGCACACAUCUGUGGAUAAAACCAGGCCUUCCCCCAUUCUCCCACUGGGUGAUCAGCCUAGCCCCUUGUGGUUGCUCCCUUUUUACUCUAAUCACUUUAUUACCUCCCCUUCCCAUCCAAUCUCUGCUCUUCCUGCCACGAGUGCAGCCCAGGAACUAGUUUGUCCAAUACAGGAGCCACCAGCCACAUGUGUCUACUGAGCACUGAAAUGUGGCCGGUCUGAAUGGCGGCAUGCUGUAUAUGUAAAAUACAUACCGGAUUUCUUUUUUUUCUUUUUCUUUUUCUCUUUUUUCUUUUCUUUUUUUUUUUUUUUGAAAUGGAGUCUCGCUCUGUCUCCCGGGAUGGAGUGCAGUAGCGCGAUCUUGGCUCACUGCAAGCUCCUCCUCCCGGGUUCACACCAUUCUCCUGCCUCAGCCUCCCGAGUAGCUGGGACUACAGGCGCCGGCCAGCACGCCAGGCUAAUUUUUUUGUAUUUUUAGUAGAGACGGGGUUUCACCGUGUUAACCAGGAUGGUCUAGAUUUCCUGACCUCGUGAUCCGCCCGCCUAGGCCUCCCAAAGUGCUGGGAUUACAGGCGUGAGCCACCGCGCCCGGCCAACACACCGGAUUUCAAAGGCUUUUCACAAAUUUAAAAAUGUAAAAUAUCUUAUUAAUGACUUUUUAUAUGGAUCACAUAUUGAAAUGAUAAUAUUUUGGAAAUAUAGGACUAAAUAAAAUAACAUCAUUAAAAUUACUUUCACCUGUUUAGACUAUUUUUAUAUGGCCACUAGGAAAUUUUAAAUUGCAUAUGUGGCUCACUUUGCGUUUAUGUUGAAUAGCAUUGCUCGGAAGACAGAUCUGACAGCAAAUUAUUUAUGGUCACUCACCUUCUUACUUGUGUGCCUAGGGCAAGCUGAAUAACCUGGCUGGGCCUCAGCUUUCUCAUUUAUGAAAUGGAGAUCCUAAUAGCACUGAUGUUGCAGAGCAGACACAGAAAUAAGAUCAUACUUUUAAAUUGCUUGUAUCAAUGUAAGUUGUACCGUCAUUGUAAAUAAAUUCUGGCCAAAUUGCUUGUAUCAAUGUAAGUUGUACCGUCAUUGUAAAUAAAUUCUGGCCGUUAGUAGUUUUCUUUCUCCUCCCCAUCAUAGGGAAUAUUCCAGCCUCUUUUGAGGCCUGCAGCAGGCCAGUUGAGGCAUCACCAUUGAAGUUGCUGGUGCAGUGUACACCCUGGCACAAGGACCUUAUCUGAGCCCCCACACUCUCCUGCUUGCUGAUGGGCAAGCCCUGGGCUGGCUGAUACCUCCAAUCUCUUUGGAGACAGCUGGCCAUAUGGCAGAAAGGCUGGAAUGGCAUCUCCACUCUGUGACCCAGUCUCCCACUUGCCCCCAAAAGAAUAUUUCUUCUGACAGUGGACAGCUGACAUAUCACCACUUUCCUUCUACUGGUACCCUGAGGGAGCCGGUCACUAUCGACUGCGGCCACAACUUCUGCCGGGCCUGCCUUACCCGCUACUGUGAGAUACCAGGCCCAGACCUGGAGGAGUCCCCUACUUGCCCACUCUGCAAAGAACCCUUCCGUCCUGGGAGCUUCCGGCCCAACUGGCAGCUGGCUAACGUGGUGGAGAACAUUGAGCGCCUCCAGCUGGUGUCCACACUGGGUUUGGGAGAGGAGGAUGUCUGCCAAGAGCACGGAGAGAAGAUCUACUUCUUCUGUGAGGAUGAUGAGAUGCAGUUGUGCGUGGUGUGCCGGGAGGCUGGGGAGCACGCUACCCACACCAUGCGCUUCCUGGAGGAUGCAGCGGCUCCCUAUAGGGAACAAAUCCAUAAGUGUCUUAAAUGUCUAAGAAAAGAGAGAGAGGAGAUUCAAGAAAUCCAGUCAAGAGAAAAUAAAAGGAUGCAAGUCCUCCUGACUCAGGUGUCCACCAAGAGACAACAGGUGAUUUCUGAGUUCGCACACCUGAGGAAGUUUCUAGAGGAACAGCAGAGCAUCCUCUUAGCACAAUUGGAGAGCCAGGAUGGGGACAUCUUGAGGCAACGGGAUGAAUUUGAUUUGCUGGUUGCUGGGGAGAUCUGCCGGUUUAGUGCUCUUAUUGAAGAACUGGAGGAGAAGAAUGAGAGGCCAGCAAGGGAGCUCCUGACGGACAUCAGAAGCACUCUAAUAAGAUGUGAAACCAGAAAGUGCCGGAAACCGGUGGCUGUGUCGCCAGAGCUGGGCCAGAGGAUUCGGGACUUUCCCCAGCAGGCCCUCCCGCUGCAGAGGGAGAUGAAGAUGUUUCUGGAAAAACUAUGCUUUGAGUUGGACUAUGAGCCAGCUCACAUUUCUCUAGACCCUCAGACUUCCCACCCCAAGCUCCUCUUGUCCGAGGACCACCAGCGAGCUCAGUUCUCCUACAAAUGGCAGAACUCACCAGACAACCCCCAGCGUUUUGACCGGGCCACCUGUGUUCUGGCCCACACUGGCAUCACAGGGGGGAGACACACGUGGGUGUGGAUGGCCAGGGUACCUGGGGACUCAGGCUGCUGCCAGUUCUGCUCACCACCAUCCGUGCUUGGCACAGAAGUAGCUGCAUAGAAAGAGCACUGGAUUUGAAGUCAGAAGACCUGGGUUCUUGAACCAGCCUGUCAACCAGUUGUAUGACUUUAAACAAGGCAUCUCACCUCUUUUCAUCUUGUUUUCUUCCAAUAAUGUUAGAGUUCAUGUAAUCACAUUCUCUAGAACCAUUUAGUUUGUGUUAACUAUGAACCAAGCAGUGUGGUGGCCACUGGUGACUUGAAAAUAUAGAGAAAAAAAAAACCUGCUCUAUAUCUGAAAGAGCUCUUGGGAAGACAGAGAAACAUAAAGAGGAAAUUACAGCACAGUGUGGUGGGUGUUACGGGAAGUCCAACCCCAGCAUUAUGGGAGUUCAGGGGAAGGGGCAUAGCCCAGCCUGGAAGGAGAGGGUGAGUGGGGGAUGGCUUUCUGAAAAGGGUGGUCUAAAGGAUGCCUAUGGUCAAUAGGGAAAAGAGGGGAAGAAGCAUCUUAAGAAGAGGAAACAGCAGAGAACUGGCUGGAUGACCUGUGACUCUGGAGCACUGGGUUGUCUCCAUUGUCAUUAUGGGCAGAUGUGUGCCAUCCCCAGCCGACGCCACUCACUGCCUCCUUCCUCCUGGUGUUGCCACUUCUGGGUGAGAUUAAGGUGCAGGGCCUGGGGGCAGGAGGACAUAAGGUAUAGCCAUAAAUCAUAACCCAGGGACCACACUCAACCCUAGGGAAAUUGUCUUCCUGAUCAGUUGAUUACCAUCUGAGGUCAAGAAAUGAGAUAGUGGGAGCAAAUGGGUCACAAAUAGCUCAGCUGUGGGCUCAGAAACUGCUAGGUAAAAGAAUUCCAGAAGGAGGCCAGGGCAUAAGUUGGAUGACCUAUGAACUUUAGUCUAAAGAAUUGAGACUACCGUAAUUGAGACUACUGUAGUGACAUCUGAGAAAUGGGAUGGAAGAGUGACCAUGUUUUAUUUUCUUGUUCUUGUCACUAUUGUAUUUUAUUUUGCAUAAUCAUGCCCUUCACUGACAGUCUCCUUAACAUCAUCUGUUUACUCUGCUCAGUGUAAACUACAAUGCUCUGUCAUCUCCCUACUGGGUCUCCUGGGAGGAGGGGAGCCAUCCAGGGUGCAAACUCAAAGGCAGAGGGCACAGCGUGCUUAGGCCCAAGCUUAGAAUUCAAUUGAGAAGUUCUGUUGUUCAUCCUUACCUCAGCAGGUAGAAAAGAGGUGGAGAUCAGAAGCCAGGGAUUAGAGAUUGAAUUGCUUUCCCUGGGAGUGUGCAGUAUCUCAUUAAAAUGUUGUAUAUUCAAAAAAAUACAGACACACACAAGUGCCUAUAUAAUGAUAAAACAUAUCCAAAGCACCCAAACCUGUGAUUCCAGAAAAGUAGAUCCUAUUUUUGUUUAUUUUUAUUGGCUUUAGCUGUGUCUUUUGAAAGGACUAUUAUCCUCUAAAAUGUAUGUGUAUGAAGAUCCUGGCUUGCAGCUCGGGAGCUUUACACACCUUGUGUCACUUUAUCUUGGUAACGAGCCAAGAUCAUGCAACCAGUUCAUCCAUGUCUGACCCAAGAGCUCUUAACUGCUAUGCUGCACUGCCUCAUUCAGAGAUAGAUGCCUGCAUGGGUCCUGGCGAUUAUUUUAAUGCUGGCUACACCCCCACAGGUGACUUGGAUUCAGAAAUACAAUUUAUAUUUCUUCUUUUUAAAUUGUUUUAUUUUAUUUUUCUUUUAAUAGUUAUAUGUCAGUGAGAACAAUUUAUAUGUCUUACACUGAGAAAUAAAACUGCUCAUAAGUGAAAACA